CCCUAUUUAAUAGAUUACUUAUCAUUACAUACGGAUCUCAGAUAGCUGCCCAUUCUUCCCAAUAUCAGUGCUUCUUGAUCAUGUCUUAUUUAAAGAAUUUUUUUUCUUUUAAUUCCUAACAUUUUACUCUCCAUUUUAUAAAUGAAGAAAUCAGGGCACAGAGGGAUUUAGAAGAUGCAUGUAAUUCUGAGACCCAGCCCACCACUUUGUUCACUUCCUGCUUAACAAAUUGAAUGGACAAGCAUUUGUUAAGUACCCUCUCUGUGCCAGGCAUAUGCCAUGUCUUGAUGGGCUCCCAGUAAAGUCUGAGUAAUUGGCCUUGUCAUGAAAUGGGACUUCUAGCAGUGCUUCAUCUCAUUGCCUGCUAAGUGGAUUUUUGAGUUGCAUCUUGACUUCCAUGCUGGAAGGAGAAAAGGAAGCAGUUUUCCUAUAGAAUACACACCUUUAGGCUGGGCGGGGAUGGUAGCUCAUGCCUGUAAUCCCAGCACUUUGAGAGGCCAAGGCAGGCACAUCACUUGAGGUUAGGAGUUCAAGGCCAGCCUGGCCAACAUGGCAAAACCCCUUCUCUACUAAAAAUACAAAAAUUAGCCAGGUAUGGUGGAGCGCACCUGUAGUCCCAGCUACUCAGGAGGCUGAGACAGGAGAAUCACUUGAACCUGGGAGGCAGAGAUUGCAGUGAGCCGAGAUUGUGCCACUGCACUCCAUCCGGGGCUACAGAGUGAGACUCCGUCCCAAAAAAAAAAAAAAAAAAAAAAGAGGAAAAAAAAAAAGAAAGCACACUCUUAAAUUGUACCCUUUUCCACUGACACCAUCUGACUUCUUCACUUCUCCUUUAUCAACUGCUCUAGUCAUAUGAAUGUGUGGCGAUAGUGCUGGUCCACAGUGUGACAUUGGGCACAUCACCUUGGACAAGCCCCACUCACCGUCACCCCUAUAUCAUUCAAGCAGCAUACAUAGUCUCUUGAUUCCAUCUGGUAAUUCUCCCUUGAAUCUAAGCCCUUGUUUCAUCCUAUUGCCAUGCUAGAGACAUCAUCAUCAUCAUCGUCGUCAUCAUUAUUUUACAUUUUUCUAACUGAUCUUUCUGCCUCAGCCUCUUUCAGCACUCCUCUAAGCAUUUUUUUUUUUUUUUUGGCUUAGAGGAGUGUUUUUAAGGGGGAACAGUGGCCAUGGUCACUGUUCCAAAAGGCAAUUCUGCUCAUGACCUGACUGUGCUAAAAUGUGUACCACUUCUCAUCAGUGUUCACAUGCAAGGCCCUCUGCAAACUGGUCCCAGUCGGCUCCUCCAGGACUCUCUAUCCAAUUUCCCCAUGUGCACUCUCAGCCACACAGAACCUCUCACCACUCUCAAGGCAGAAAAGCUGCUGGGUACAUCUUCCCCACUCCUAAGUGACACUUCCAUCACUUUUUUGCACUGUGUAUUACUAUUCACUUUCCAGCUCCAGAUCAGAUGUCCUCUGUGAAGUUUCUCUUAAUUCCCCCAAACAAACCUCAACCUCUGCCCCCGCCAACUCCUCAGCAUUUUCUUCAAACCUCAUUCAUACCUCCAUUCUGUAACUUAUUGCAUCAGCAUACAAGCAUACAGUUGUCCCUCUCCCCUACCAGGUUGUAAAGCUUUUCAAAUACAGCAUUUAAAAAAAAAAGAAAAAAGAUUUUUGUUACUCUAAGGUCUAGAAAAGUGCCAAGAAAUACCCAUGAAUCGUGAAUGCACCUCUGGCCUGAGUUUUUGCCUACACAUUCUACCGGCUGAGCUUAAUCCACUUCAGAGGUUUCAUUAAGAUACAGCCACUUUAGCUUCACAAUGAAUACAUUAGCAUUUUGUAAUCCUAGAGCACUCUGCUCCAUGUUUCCAAACACGUAAGAUCCCUUAAUUCUGUUUUCAACAGAAGACAGCUCAAAUGCCCUAUAUUACCUUCUUGGAAAGAGGCAUUCAUCUCCUCUUUGUCUUUUGCAAUGGAUUUUGGUCCAUUGAUCAUAAUGACAUAUGACAUCUAUUUCAACACUUAGUAUGUGGCAAACAUGGUGCUUUGUAUGUAUUAUCACUUUUACUGCCUACAUCAACAACAUUAUGAUGUAGGUGGUUCUGUUCCCUCAGUUUUGGAGAACAGGAAAUGGAGGCACAGAAAGAUGACAUAACUAGUCUGAGGAUGUAGGGAAAAAAAAAAAAAAGCAAACAAAGCUGCUUUUGCUAUUCUCUCACUCACAACAAUCAAUACAGAAGACUUCUGGGACCUCUGGUCACCAGGAAGUGUGUGGAAAUUUCUCCCUGCCAACAACCAGUCAAUCAGUUCUGCAGUGGCCACCAGCUGCAGAAUUGUCCUCGAAUUCAAUUCAAUUCUGACACUCCUGCUACCUGGAGAGAACAGCAGAUCCCAUAGGUUAAGGGCUCAGGCCCACAGGACUUCUUUCCCCACUUUCAAGGCCAGUAGCAAGCCCCAAGUUGUUUUACCUGUGCUUCUGACUGACCAGCUCUAUAUUGGGGUUCCCUCGACCCUCUCCUUGGGUUUGACUAAUUUGUUAGUACUGGCUCGCAGAACUCAGGAAAAGACUGACUUACUUUUAUCAGUACAUUUGUAUAAAGGAUAUCACAAAGGAUCAAGAUGAAGAGAUGCACAGGGCAAGGCACCUGCAAAGGAGAAUGGAGCUUCGAUGCUCUACUGCCCUUCAGGAACCUCCAUGUGUUCAGCUAUCGGGAAACUCUCUGAACCCAGUCCUUUUGAGCUUUUAUCAUUAUGUAGUGACCAGCCUAGAAGCUGAAGCUACCCAGCGGCUGCCAGCUAGCAGUCAUCUCAUUAGCAUACAAAAAAGACUAUCAUGUUGGAAUCAUGUGAAAUCACGUUGGACAUUCCAAGGAUUUUAGGAGUUGUGUGCCAGGAAACCUGGACAAAGACCAACUAUACAUUUCACGAUGUCAGAACGACAGCCAUUGUUUGAUGUCCUGUGACUGAGAAACCAGGCUUUAAACUUUAUGCCUUUGGAGAUGGAGCCCAAGAUGAGCAAACUGGCCUUUGGCUGUCAGAGAAGUUCCACAUCAGAUGAUGACUCUGGCUGUGCAUUGGAGGAGUACGCCUGGGUCCCCCCGGGCCUGAGACCAGAGCAGAUCCAGCUCUAUUUUGCUUGCUUACCAGAGGAAAAAGUUCCUUACGUUAACAGCCCCGGAGAGAAGCAUCGGAUUAAACAGCUUUUGUACCAGUUACCACCACAUGAUAAUGAGGUACGGUAUUGCCAGUCUUUGAGUGAAGAGGAGAAAAAAGAGUUGCAGGUGUUCAGUGCUCAGCGGAAGAAAGAAGCACUGGGAAGAGGAACAAUUAAGCUUCUGUCCAGAGCAGUCAUGCAUGCUGUGUGUGAGCAGUGUGGUUUGAAGAUAAAUGGAGGUGAAGUUGCAGUGUUCGCCUCCCGUGCGGGCCCUGGUGUGUGCUGGCACCCAUCCUGUUUUGUCUGUUUCACGUGUAAUGAGCUGCUGGUCGACCUCAUCUAUUUUUAUCAGGAUGGAAAAAUUCACUGUGGCAGGCACCAUGCAGAACUGCUCAAACCACGGUGCUCAGCAUGUGACGAGAUAAUUUUUGCUGAUGAGUGCACAGAAGCUGAGGGUCGCCAUUGGCACAUGAAACACUUCUGCUGCCUUGAGUGUGAAACGGUCCUGGGAGGACAGAGGUAUAUCAUGAAGGACGGCCGCCCCUUCUGCUGUGGCUGUUUUGAGUCUCUCUAUGCGGAGUACUGUGAAACCUGUGGGGAACAUAUUGGUGUGGACCAUGCACAGAUGACCUAUGACGGGCAGCACUGGCACGCCACGGAAGCCUGCUUUUCUUGUGCCCAGUGUAAAGCCUCUUUGUUGGGAUGUCCCUUCCUUCCCAAACAGGGUCAGAUUUACUGCUCAAAAACGUGCAGUCUUGGUGAAGACGUCCAUGCCUCUGAUUCUUCCGACUCUGCAUUUCAGUCAGCUCGAUCAAGAGACUCCCGAAGAAGUGUCCGAAUGGGCAAGAGCAGCCGGUCAGCAGAUCAGUGUAGACAGUCUCUCCUCUUAUCGCCUGCUCUGAACUACAAGUUUCCUGGCCUCUCAGGCAAUGCUGAUGACACCCUUUCUCGAAAAUUGGAUGAUCUGAGUCUCUCCAGACAAGGAACAAGUUUUGCCAGUGAAGAAUUUUGGAAAGGCAGAGUAGAGCAGGAAACUCCAGAAGACCCUGAAGAAUGGGCUGAUCAUGAAGAUUAUAUGACGCAGCUCCUCCUCAAGUUUGGUGAUAAAAGCCUCUUUCAGCCACAGCCCAAUGAGAUGGAUAUUCGAGCCAGUGAGCACUGGAUAUCUGAUAACAUGGUUAAAAGUAAGACCGAGUUAAAGCAAAAUAACCAGAGCCUUGCAAGUAAAAAAUACCAGUCUGAUAUGUACUGGGCACAGUCACAAGAUGGACUGGGCGAUUCUGCUUAUGGCAGCCACCCAGGCCCUGCAAGCAGUAGAAGGCUUCAGGAAUUGGAACUGGACCAUGGGGCUUCAGGGUAUAAUCAUGAUGAAACACAGUGGUAUGAAGAUUCCCUGGAGUGUCUGUCAGACCUGAAACCAGAGCAAAGUGUUCGGGAUUCGAUGGAUUCUUUGGCAUUGUCCAAUAUCACAGGGGCUUCGGUGGAUGGAGAAAACAAGCCAAGGCCAUCAUUGUAUUCUCUGCAAAAUUUUGAGGAGAUGGAAACAGAAGAUUGUGAGAAGAUGAGCAAUAUGGGAACUUUGAACUCUUCCAUGCUGCACAGGAGUGCAGAGUCCUUAAAGAGUCUAAGUUCAGAGUUGUGUCCAGAGAAAAUCCUGCCUGAAGAGAAGCCAGUACAUCUGCCAGUGCUCAGAAGGUCCAAGUCUCAAUCCAGACCCCAGCAGGUCAAGUUUUCUGAUGAUGUCAUUGACAAUGGGAACUAUGACAUUGAAAUCCGGCAGCCUCCGAUGAGUGAAAGGACUCGGAGACGCGUCUACAAUUUUGAAGAGAGGGGAUCCAGGUCUCAUCACCACCGCCGCCGGAGAAGUAGAAAGUCCCGCUCCGACAAUGCCCUGAAUCUUGUUACAGAAAGAAAAUACUCUCCCAAGGACAGACUGCGGCUGUACACCCCCGAUAACUAUGAGAAAUUUAUACAGAAUAAAAGUGCCCGGGAGAUCCAAGCAUACAUCCAGAAUGCUGAUCUCUACGGACAGUACGCCCAUGCCACUUCCGAUUAUGGCCUGCAGAACCCAGGAAUGAAUCGGUUUCUGGGACUCUACGGCGAGGAUGAUGAUUCCUGGUGUUCUUCCUCCUCCUCCUCUUCCGACUCGGAAGAAGAAGGAUAUUUUCUUGGACAACCAAUCCCUCAACCCCGGCCACAGAGAUUUGCCUACUAUACAGAUGACCUUUCUAGUCCACCAUCUGCACUUCCCACCCCUCAGUUUGGUCAGAGGACAACAAAAUCCAAGAAGAAAAAGGGACACAAGGGCAAAAAUUGUAUUAUUUCUUAACCAAGUAGUGAUGCAGAGCAUUUGUUUAAAACUUAGCCAUUAACCGUCUGAAUCGUUUCCUUUUCUUCCGUAGGAAAGUUGUGAAAAUAGUUUAAAGUGCUUUCUUUGCCCAUGUAAAUGAGAACUCAACUGCUGUUUACAGUGUCAGAUUAACAUUUGAAAGGUGUGAUUUCUCCAAUUUACCCUCUUUGGAUGGUGCCAGGUGGACGUGACAUCUCGUGCCUGUCCGGUGCGGGUGCGUUACAGAUGGACGUAGCUGCUUUGGUUUUCCAGUCCUCAAGGGAAUACUGAAGAUGCUGACUGAAGGGGAUUGGAUGUUGAUUUUAGAAGAUGGAGAACUCCAGCCACCUUUGUAAAGCACUAGUGUUUGUCAUUUAUGUAAGUCAGGUCGGCUCAGGUCUUGAUAGUCCGUCUUGGUGUGAGGCAUGCCUGUCACGAUGACCUAGCUAACACUGUGCAUCUUAUUGUGAGGCCAGCUUGUCCCCUCGAACCCUCUUUGGCCAGGUAAACAUUGUAUUGUAUCAGCGCCAGCUACAGAUUGAAAAAAAAAAACAAAAAACAUUGCUAUUUAUAACUUAGUAUUUCAUAGACUUAAGUGUAUUCCUAAUUUAACGGUGCAAAUAUUAAUGUAUAUACUGUACAGUUCAGAUUUUAAAGCUGAUAUUUUUAUAUCCCUGAAUUGUAAGCCGUUUGUUACGCUGCAGUGCUAGAUUUGCCAGGGAACCAGAAUUUAUGGAUGAACUGAUUGCUUAUAUUUUAGUCAGGGUUUAUAAAUGUAGAUGGUCAAAUUUACAUUGCCUAGUGAUGGAAAAUUCAACUUUUUUUGAUUUUUUUUUCCAAUAUUAAAAAAGGCUCUGUAUGCAUGGUGGGGCUAUGUAAGUACUCUUUAAAACUAUGGCCCUAUUAAUCUUACAAGUGUUACUUAUGGGUCAAGCAAUGUAAACUGUAUAAAUGUAAAAACAACCCCUCCACACACAUAACCCCUGGAAUAUAUGGUAAAAACAAGUAGAAGCUGUUUCAGCGAGUGGGUUUUUUCCCCCUGCCUGCGGGGGGUGCCUUUCUCAUUUUCAGCAAGGUGAUGAUUAUCUCAUGGGAAAUGACAAAGAUCUGCUUUUGUGGCAGAGGACUUUGUAGAUUUGUUAUUUUAAGAGAGGUUAUUCCUUUUUAUUCCUUCCCUCCCACUAAUUUGUUGGCCUUUAACAGCAAUUUUGAAAACUGGGUCUUCUGGUUAUGUUUUUGUUUUAAAAUCUUUAAAUUAGAGGAUGCUGUGCCAUUGAGUACUGUAAGUUAAUAUGAGGUUCUGGUUCAAGGAAAACUUACGUUGGAUCUGAACCAAUGAGCAGAUAUUUUGAUAUGUGCCACUCUUGCAUAUACAUCUCAGUCCUAACUAAAGGUUCUAGUGGCAUCCAGGACCUUUAGGGAGGCAUUUAAUAAACACUUAAUAAAUAACAAAACUACCUUUCUGAAUAUAAAUCUUUGCAAAUGUAUCCAGAUAACUUCCAUUUUGUGCCUGUGUUCAGGCAUGAUUUAUUUUGCAGUUGCCCUACCAUUAACAGACCUCCAUUUGUCUCGUGUGUCCACACGCCCCACUUGUAGGCCAGAAAUAGGGCUUCAGACACAGAGGCUUAUUUUUUCCAUAUAGACUGGAGUGGGGAAAAUUUGGCCUUAGGGAGGACAGACACAAGUCCAAUGGGUAAACCAGCGAGUAGUAGGUGGACAGCCGUCCCACACAAGGGUUUGUAUCUGGGCUACACAGAUUCCCUUCAGAAAAGCACCAAUGGUGAGAGAGUUCUUCACUCAGUAACUUACAUUCCCUGGUCUGGUGCCUUUAAAAAACCAUCAGCAAUGAAAAGGAAGUGCAUACACAUGACAAAAAAAUUCAAAUAGGGCAAAAGUCAGAGACAGCAUCUCCUUUCCAUUCUUCAUCCCAGUCCCCCAGGUCCUCUCCCCAGAAGUAACCACUCUUACCCAGUUUUAGUGUCUCCUUCAGACAUUCAAAGCACAUUCGUAUAAAUGUGUCUUUUAAAAGUGGUAGUGACCUAUAUGUGCUGUGACAUGCUUUUUUCCCUUUGUAUGUGGACAUUUCACGUUAGUGCAUAUAGGUCUACCCAUUCUUUCAGUGACUGCUUAAUAGCCUACUCCUAAUGAUGGAGUUGACUUUCCUCAUACAUUAUGCUACACUGGCACAUGUGCACAUAAAUCGGGAGCAGCGUAGUUACUGGGACAAAGGUUACGUAUUUAAGACUGAUGGAUAUUGCCAAUUUUCCUCCAAAAGAAAUUCUCCUGAUUUACAUUAAUGUAAUGUAAAUGAGAGUGUUUGUUCCAUCACAACCUCUCAAUGUAUUAGCAGAUUUCUUGAUUUUGAAGAAAUUUUCAGAACCUGUGCUGCCACAAGUGGGCAUCCUUUUAGAAAAGACUGUUGCAAUAUGUUGCUUAUAAAGGAUGGAUAAUAAAUAGUAAACAGGUGAUACUUAGCCUGAAGAAAUGCAGGUAUAAGGUGAAGGUACUGCCCUCACUUUUCAAGUACAUUCUCAAAAGAUAGGGGUAACAUAGCCUGCCAAAGGCUUAAGGAAAUGCAGAUAUUUAUUCACAAUAAUAAUGUGACUUUCUUUUCCUUUUUUUUUUUUUUUUGAGAUGGAGUUUCGCUCCUGUUGCCCAGGCUGGAGCGCAACGGCACAAUCUCAGUUCACUGCAACCUCUGCCUCCCGGGUUCAAGCAAUUCUCCUGUCUCAGCCUCCGGAGUAGCUGAGAUUACAGGUGCCUGCCACCAUGCUCGGCUAAUUUUUUAUAUUUUUAGUAGAGACAGUGUUUCACCAAGUUGGCCAGGCUGGUCUCGAACUCCUGACCUUCAGGUGAUCCACCUGCCUCAGCCUCCCAAAGUGCAGGGGAUUACAGGCAUGAGCCACUGCGUCUGGCAAUAAUGUAACUUUGAAGCUUAAAAAUUAAUCCCAGUUUGUAGCAAUAACAGAAGACUAUCUACAACGGAAGAAAGAAGCAACUGCCUUACAGUUCUGUAAAGAAUUGGCAAGAAAAUAAAGCCUAUAGUUGCCGA